AGGCGCGCGGGGAUUGGCGGGAUGCGGCGCGCCGCGCGGUGAGUGGGGUCCAGGGAAACGGGGUCAGCUGGGGGUGGCAGUUCCAGGCCGCGAGGCCGGGCUCCUGGGUCGGUGGGCUGGUGUCUUGGCGGACGUCCCGCAGCUGCCGCGUGGAUCCGAGCCGGGGCACCCGCCGUGACUGGGACAGCCCCCAGGGCGCUCUCGGCCCCAUCCCGAGUAGCGCGGCCUGGCUGCUGCCGCCAUCAAGCACGUUCGAGCCAAAAGCUCCUAACGAGUCACUCGUUAGACACGUGUGCGGAGCCUGUGUCCCAGGCCAGUGCUGUCCCGUGGAGAUAGAUUGCAAGCCGCUAGGGAAUUUUUUAACUUUCUAGUAGGUGUACGAAAAAAGUAAAACGAAACAAAUCAAUUGGAGUAAAUCCAUAAAUAUAUUCAAACUAUUAUUUCAAUUGUAUGUGAAAAAAUUAUUGGGAUAUUCUUUGUACUAUUCUUAGAAAUCCAUUGUGUGUCCAACCCAAACAUCACAGUUGGACUCACCACAUCUCCUGUACUUCGUAGCCCUAGGUGGCUAGUGGCAUAAGACACAAAAAUCUCAGCUCUCCUGGAGCUUAUGGUCUAGUUGGAGCAGGCAGACAAUACAUUUAAAAUAUACAGUUUGUUAGAAGGUGCCGGAGAGCUGGAUGGAGGCAGAUCGGGAAUUCCAUUUGGGGCAAACUGAACUUGAUUGAGACCCUGGUAGUUGUCCAGAUGGAACAGGACACCUGAGUCUAGGGUUCGGGAAGAACUCCAGAUGGGACAAACACUCCUAGCUUUCCUUUUCUCUUUUUGGAUGACCGCUACAGGGUGAGACAUCGGUAUCCAGGCACGAUAAAUUUCCAAGUGGACACAAUGUCUGGUGUCAACUACAGCUGUUCUCCUUCUUUUCCCAGUAUCCUUUGGGUGCAGUGAGACACCAGGAGAGCUGCUGCUUUGGGGGAUGGACAGGGGCAGCAGGAAUGCCUUUGUGUUUUCGCAGUGAACCUCCUUGGCCUGGGCGAAGCUGUGUGGACCAAGCAAGUCAGGAGUGUGGCCAUGUUUUCUGAGCAGGCUGCCCAGAGGGCCCACACUCUACUGUCCCCACCAUCAGCCAACAAUGCCACCUUUGCCCGGGUGCCAGUGGCAACCUACACCAACUCCUCACAACCCUUCCGGCUAGGAGAGCGCAGCUUUAGCCGGCAGUAUGCCCACAUUUAUGCCACCCGCCUCAUCCAAAUGAGACCCUUCCUGGAGAACCGGGCCCAGCAGCACUGGGGCAGUGGAGUGGGAGUGAAGAAGCUGUGUGAACUGCAGCCUGAGGAGAAGUGCUGUGUGGUGGGCACUCUGUUCAAGGCCAUGCCGCUGCAGCCCUCCAUCCUGCGGGAGGUCAGCGAGGAGCACAACCUGCUCCCCCAGCCUCCUCGGAGUAAAUACAUACACCCAGAUGACGAGCUGGUCUUGGAAGAUGAACUGCAGCGUAUCAAACUAAAAGGCACCAUUGACGUGUCAAAGCUGGUUACGGGGACUGUCCUGGCUGUGUUUGGCUCCGUGAGAGACGACGGGAAGUUUCUGGUGGAGGACUAUUGCUUUGCUGACCUUGCUCCCCAGAAGCCCGCACCCCCACUUGACACAGAUAGGUUUGUGCUACUGGUGUCCGGCCUGGGCCUGGGUGGCGGUGGAGGCGAGAGCCUGCUGGGCACCCAGCUGCUGGUGGAUGUGGUGACGGGGCAGCUUGGGGACGAAGGGGAGCAGUGCAGCGCCGCCCACGUCUCCCGGGUUAUCCUCGCUGGCAACCUCCUCAGCCACAGCACCCAGAGCAGGGAUUCUAUCAAUAAGGCCAAAUACCUCACCAAGAAAACCCAGGCAGCCAGCGUGGAGGCUGUUAAGAUGCUGGAUGAGAUCCUCCUGCAGCUGAGCGCCUCAGUGCCCGUGGACGUGAUGCCAGGCGAGUUUGAUCCCACCAAUUACACGCUCCCCCAGCAGCCCCUCCACCCCUGCAUGUUCCCGCUGGCCACUGCCUACUCCACGCUCCAGCUGGUCACCAACCCCUACCAGGCCACCAUUGAUGGAGUCAGAUUUUUGGGGACAUCAGGACAGAACGUGAGUGACAUUUUCCGAUACAGCAGCAUGGAGGAUCACUUGGAGAUCCUGGAGUGGACCCUGCGGGUCCGUCACAUCAGCCCCACAGCCCCUGACACUCUAGGUUGUUACCCCUUCUACAAAACUGACCCGUUCAUCUUCCCAGAGUGCCCGCAUGUCUACUUUUGUGGCAACACCCCCAGCUUUGGCUCCAAAAUCAUCCGAGGUCCUGAGGACCAGACAGUGCUGUUGGUGACUGUCCCUGACUUCAGUGCCACGCAGACCGCCUGCCUUGUGAACCUGCGCAGCCUGGCCUGCCAGCCCAUCAGCUUCUCGGGCUUCGGGGCAGAGGACGAUGACCUGGGAGGCCUGGGGCUGGGCCCCUGACUCAAAAAAGUGGUUUUGACCAGAGAGGCCCAGAUGGAGGCUGUUCAUUCCCUGCAGUGUCGGCAUUGUAAAUAAAGCCUGAGCACUUGCUGAUGCGAGCCUUGA